AGUAGCCGCCUGCUAGUGGCGCUGCUAGCCGGCCGGCGCAGGCUGCCGAGCGGGUGAGCGCGCAGGCCAGGCCAAAGCCCUGGUACCCGCGCGGUGCGGGCCUCAGUCUGCGGCCAUGGGGGCGUCCGCGCGGCUGCUGCGAGCGGUGAUCAUGGGGGCCCCGGGCUCGGGCAAGGGCACCGUGUCGUCGCGCAUCACUACACACUUCGAGCUGAAGCACCUCUCCAGCGGGGACCUGCUCCGGGACAACAUGCUGCGGGGCACAGAAAUUGGCGUGUUAGCCAAGGCUUUCAUUGACCAAGGGAAACUCAUCCCAGAUGAUGUCAUGACUCGGCUGGCCCUUCAUGAGCUGAAAAAUCUCACCCAGUAUAGCUGGCUGUUGGAUGGUUUUCCAAGGACACUUCCACAGGCAGAAGCCCUAGAUAGAGCUUAUCAGAUCGACACAGUGAUUAACCUGAAUGUGCCCUUUGAGGUCAUUAAACAACGCCUUACUGCUCGCUGGAUUCAUCCCGCCAGUGGCCGAGUCUAUAACAUUGAAUUCAACCCUCCCAAAACUGUGGGCAUUGAUGACCUGACUGGGGAGCCUCUCAUUCAGCGUGAGGAUGAUAAACCAGAGACGGUUAUCAAGAGACUAAAGGCUUAUGAAGACCAAACAAAGCCAGUCCUGGAAUAUUACCAGAAAAAAGGGGUGCUGGAAACAUUCUCCGGAACAGAAACCAACAAGAUUUGGCCCUAUGUAUAUGCUUUCCUACAAACUAAAGUUCCACAAAGAAGCCAGAAAGCUUCAGUUACUCCAUGAGGAGAAAUGUGUGUAACUAUUAAUAGUAAGAUGGGCAAACCUCCUAGUCCUUGCAUUUAGAAGCUGCUUUUCCUAAGACUUCUAGUAUGUAUGAAUUCUUUGAAAAUUAUAUUACUUUUAUUUCUACUGAUUUUAUUUUGGAUACUAAGGAUGUGCCAAAUGAUUCGGAUACUAAGAUGCAUCGUUUGAAAUCAUCUAGUGUGUUGUAUGCAGUUAUCCUCAAAAACAUCAGCGAUGUCUGAACCUUUAAAACAUCUGUUAGAGCAAAAUUAAAAGAGCAUUUGGUAGUAAUCUAACUUUUUGUUCAGUUAAUAAGUGGUUGAUAAAGUUUCCAUAUUUUUCUGGAAAAGUUAAAAAAAGUUACAUGUCAUUUGGAGAAAAUACGUAAUCAGAAAUUUGUGCAUAGAUUGAUGCCAAAAAAGACAUUUCCAGCAUUGUGGAACAUGGUGAGACACUAUAUAAAAUUCCAGAAAGAAAGCAACUGGAUUUACAGAUUUAUUGUGAGACACAAAUUCACUGCUGCCUUUACACUAAGAAAUGUAUAUGUUAACCAUAUAUGCUGUAUUUAUUUUGUCGUUAAGCAUACUUUCAGUUUACUCAGAAUUUUCAAUUUGCUAUAAAGAUGUAUCAAUUAGCAUAUAGAAAAAUAUUACUUUAAGAUGACUUGUUUCCUUUGAAAAUACCUGUGUACUGAGGGUUAUGAUUUGUGUCAAAAAUUGACAUAAGUGCUUUUACAAGCACCAAAGUUGAAUGAAUUUUCAACAAAAUGUAAUUAAAGUCUAUGUUUUCAGUUAUGACUCAGGUUAAGAAAUGUGUUUUAGGAUCUACUUGCUGGUUUUUCUUUUUGAUCCAAAUGUGUGAUCUGCCCUGAUAAAUAACAAGUUAUAGUACCAUCUCCCCCGCCAAUAAAAAAGAGAAGAAAAAAGAGAAACCCGUGGCACUAUGUAAAUAAAGUAAGCAUACUUUGUUGUUAGUAAAUAGAUGAGGCAUGCCUGGGAAAUGCUCCCUUGGCAUAAAUAGCAAUCAAUCAUAAUUAGUAAACAGGUGUACCAAUAAAAAGAAUUUACAUGAUAGGUUAACAAGGACCAGGAAAGUGAGUUUCCUGAAGGAGUUCUUUGUUCCUGAUCAAAGAAAUUGAUACCUGUUAGCAUUCACUGCCACCAUAUUUUAAGGAGAAAGAACUCUAUUGGUGUCGUCUGAGCAGCCAUUUAAAAAUUGGAAUCUAAAGGAUGGUUGCUGAUGUACUGUGUGGUCUGGUAGAAGUGGGGAAAUAUGAGAGAUGGAGGAAAAACUUGAUUAUGUCUUCCAUGGCAUAUUUACUCUUACUUUACUUCGUGCCAAAUCAAAUGAAACAAGCCGUCUUACAAGUCGUUAUUGCCUUUAAAAAUCUGUUCCGUUUUUUUCCCAGGUACUUAAAAUACAAGUGCCAGUAAGUGGUUCUUAUGUGUUUUGGGGGGAAAAUUUUAUUUCCCUUUUCUUCUGAUAUUUAAAAAAUUCAUCGAUCUUUCAAGAUGAACCAAGGUUUUUUAAAAGAAAUAUAGGAAACACUUCAUUCUUUAUAAAACUUUCUAUAAUGCCUUAUUUGAAUGUUAAUCUUAUGUGCUUUCUAAAAAAUGUUGUGAAAUACCAAACUUAUGGAUUAUCACUAGGUUAUCAAGCAUAUAUUAGUCUUUAUCAGAAUAAAAUGAAAUUUCAUAACUGUGGCUAUUACUUUGUUCUUGGUCCUUCACAGGGCCUGCUCCAUCCCACCUUCCUUUCUGCUGCCUGAUGUCUCAAUGGCUUCUGAAUGACUGUUCUAAUAAAUGAUCUUAAAACAGUCCAUAGGCUGGUUUCAGUUUAUGCAAUACUUCAUCUCCUGCUAUGGUAGCCAUACCGGCCUUCAUAAUACCCUUAGGGGAUUUGGAAAUCAAAGUGAGCAGUGGAAGAACAUGGCUAUGAGAAUUAAGACUCUUAUUUCCUGUGACCAUUCCCUCCCCACCCGCAAACACUUAGCCCAAAGUUUUGCACAUACAUUCAUUACUUUAGGAAUGAAUAUGACUGUAAUACAACUUUUUUCUUUAUUUUUUUUUAGACAGGGCCUCACUCUGUUGCCCAGACUAGAGUGCAGUGGCAUAAUUGGGUCACUGUAACGUUGAACUCCUGGGCUCACGCAAUUCUUCUACCUCAGCCUCCCAAGUAGCUGAAACUACAGGUAUGUACCACCAUGCCUGGCUAAUUUUAUUUUUUUGUAGAGACGGCGUCUCGAUAUGUUGCCCAGGCUAGUCUCCUGGCCUCAAACAGUCUUCCUGAUUCAGCUUCCCAAGUGCUGAGAUUACAGGUGUAAGCCACUGCCCCCACCCAAAAAAAUAAUUCUGUAAUGACCAUCAUUAAGAUUUAUGUACCACAUGGAAAUACAUGUAUGGAGCUGAAUGCCAUGGCUAGGAGAAACUACUAUACUUUUGUUAAAAGCCAAUGAGAGGCCGGGCGCGGUGGCUCACGCCUGUAAUCCCAGCACUUUGGGAGGCCGAGGCGGGCGGAUCACGAGGUCAGGAGAUCGAGACCAUCCUGGCUAACACGGUGAAACCCCGUCUCUACUAAAAAUACAAAAAAAAAAAAAAAAAAUUAGCCGGGCAUGGUGGCGGGCGCCUGUAGUCCCAGCUACUCGGGAGGUUGAGGCAGGAGAAUGGUGUGAAUCCGGGAGGCGGAGGUUGCAGUGAGCUGAGAUCGUGCCACUGCACUCCAGCCUGGGCGACAGAGGGAGACUCCGUCUCAAAAAAAAAAGCCAGGGAGAACAGCACCUCAACUGAUUUAUUUUAUAGAGUAAAAGUUAUUUUGCUAUACCUUUUGUAAGCAGCGUGUACUGUGGGAAAUGCAAACUAGCAGUUGUUAGCACCAUCCAGAAAUUUCUGUCAGUUCCAUUUCAAAUAGUUUAAAUACUGGCUCAAAUCUCUAAACCCCACCCUAUGGCUACUUUUCCCCCAGCUAUAUAUAAUGGCAUUCUAGCAAGAUAUUUUGGAUCCUCAUAACUUGUGACAAAACUGCCCUAUACUAACAACAAAUCAUUGUAAUUAUAGAUCUCAAAUUAUGUUAAAUUGCUAUAGUUGCAACCAACAGCAAGAAUUUGUAUUUUAGAAUAUGUUGUGUCUUCUCAUUGACCAAAAAAUAAAAAUAAAAAUAAAAAUAAAUCCUCAGGCCCUGAUAAACUGUAGAAAUAGCUUUUCUAUCUUUGCAGUUAAAGAUUUUCAUCUUGGAAGUUAUGGUUAAAAAAUUUUUAAACAGUUAAAAUAGUGUAGCUGUGCUUAAAGCUUCUGGUAAAAGCCAGUAUGCUUUGUAGAGCCCUUAUCCCCCUCCUGCUUUUUAUUUGUUUUUAGCUCACUAAAUAAUAUAAACACUGAUUUUUCCAUAUAUAGCACUGAAUAAACUGUCAUGCCUAAGUGUAAA